GAGUGUGUCUGCGCGCAAGCUCGUGUAAAGAGCGAAGGCGAGGUGGGGGCGAGUGUGCAUGAGCGCGAGCAUAAGUGUACUGUCAACAGUGAGAUUAAGCUGUUCCUUUAACUGAGUGCAGCCACUAGUCUCCUGGUUCCUGCCAAGGAGGAAAUUCAGAGGCUGAGGAGGGAGGAUCGCUUGAGCUGAGGAGUUCAAGGCUGCAGUGAGCUAUGAUGGUGCCACUGCACACCAGCCUAGGUGAGAGAGUGAGACUCUGUCUUAAAAAAAAAAAAAAAAAAGACAUUCAGGAAAGCUUGGACCACCAGUAUACUCAAUUAGACCAUUAAAUCUUAAAUCGUCACAUGGCCUUGAGAAAGCCACAUAGCAUCUCUGAAAUAUAGCAUAUCAUAGCAUCUCUGAAACAUAGCAUAUCUGAAAAUAAAUACACCCUCUUUGCUUACCUCACAGGUUCUUGGGGGAAUAUUAAAUGAUAUAUUAUGUACGUGCUUUAUAAGCAGUAAAAUAUUACAUAAUGCUGUGGUAACCCUCACAGGGUUGAUAAGCUAGGGAGCCUUAAGCAUCACCUAUUACCCCGUAUUUAUUGUGUACUGGGCCUUCUUCUAGGCACUUCACCGAUCUUAAGCCCUUGAAUCUGCUGAGCAUCCCAAUGGGGCAGGUACUGAACAGGGAAGUUAAGUGGCUUGUCUAGGGUCACACAGUAAGUGGCAGAGCUGACAUUCAAGGCCAGGUAGUCAGGUUCCAGAACACACAUUGUUAAACACCAGACCAAGCUGCCUCCUGUGUGCCCCACUGACACUUCCUGUGUCCUCCUCCAUGAGCCCCUGGCAGAGAUGACAAUUGCUUGCCUUAACAAUAGAUAAGCUACCAGAAGUCAGGGCCUGUGCCUCAUUCACACACGUCCACAGUGCCUGCCACAUAGCUAGAGUUCAGUAGAUAUUUGUUGAAUGAACAAAUACCCUCCAGGGAGGGAUACAAUAAGUCUGAUACAACUACUGUAUUUUUCCUUCAUUUUUUCUUGGCUAACCACACUCAUUUCCUUCAGUUGUUUCCAAAAGGAGGUUGGCAUCUCUCACUGUCCUCAUUGACCUCCUUUGCACUUUCUCCACGUCAACAGUGACCCAUCUAAAGCCGACUACUGUGACAUGAACACUGCACUUGAAGAGCCUGACCAGCGCUGGGCUCAGUAGAACUAUCCUUUCUUCUCCCAUGGUGUAUCCUCACUGUCCAGGACUCUCUUCUCAGAAGCCCACUCCUUCCCCUGUGCUGUUUAUAUGCUUAAUGAAACCAAGUACCCAAAGUGACCGUUCAACUGUUACUAGGCAGCUAAGUAGACUCCAUUAAACCUUUUCCUUCCUUCCUCCCCUUCUUUCUUUCUCUCCCAUUCUUCUUUCAUUCUUCUCGUCCUUCCUUCUAUCCUUUCUUCCUUCCUGCCUCCUUUUCUUCCUCUCCUCUGCCCUUUCUUUCAGGUCUUUUUUGUGGUAGGAACUGGUAAGAAAAGGAAAGGAAUUCCCUAAGAUUUUAAGGAAACAACAACAAAAACCAGGUUAUGUUUGGUGAGAGAGUUGGGGCAAGAAACUGCAUCUUCUAAUAUGGAAUCCAGAUUUGGACUGAGCAACAAAUUUGAAUCUGAAUUCCCUUCUUCAUUAACUGGAAAAGUAGCUCCUGAAGAAUUUAAAGCCAGCAUCAACAGAGUUAACAGUUGUCUUAAGAAGAACCUUCCUGUUAAUGUACGUUGGCUACUUUGUGGCUGCCUUUGUUGCUGCUGCACAUUAGGUUGCAGUAUGUGGCCAGUUAUUUGCCUCAGUAAAAGAACACGAAGAUCGAUUGAGAAGUUAUUAGAAUGGGAAAACAAUAGGUUAUACCACAAGCUGUGCUUGCAUUGGAGACUGAGCAAAAGGAAAUGUGAAACGAAUAACAUGAUGGAAUAUGUCAUCCUCAUAGAAUUUUUACCAAAGACACCGAUUUUUCGACCAGAUUAGCAUUUACUUUAUUUAUAGAGACUUUCCAAGUAUGUUGUCUUUCCAAUGGUGCCUUGCUUGGUGCUCUCCUGGUGGUGACAUAACAUUGGUUCUACAGAAUCGUGUGGUGUUUUUUUUGUUUUUGUUUUUGUUUUUUUUUUAAAUAACCGCAUGUUCUAAGUGUGCAUUUUUGUCAAUCUUUGCAACAGUUAUUUCAUACAGAUGUUUAAUACUUAAGUUAUUGUGCUCUUUUCUGUUAUGUAUUCUGAUUUUCAAGGAUUACUUUUUUGUAUUAUCAAAAAAAUACAUUUGAACUUAGCAUAAAAA